AGGAGCCGCCGGCAAGGGGGCAACGAGGAAGCUCUUAAGAGCGCGGCCGGAAAGCAGUUGAGUUACAGACAUCCUGCCAAAAUGAUUUCUUCAAAGCCCAGACUUGUCGUACCCUAUGGCCUCAAGACUCUGCUCGAGGGAAUUAGCAGAGCUGUUCUCAAAACCAACCCAUCAAACAUCAACCAGUUUGCAGCAGCUUAUUUUCAAGAACUUACUAUGUAUAGAGGGAAUACUACUAUGGAUAUAAAAGAUCUGGUUAAACAAUUUCAUCAGAUUAAAGUAGAGAAAUGGUCAGAAGGAACGACACCACAGAAGAAAUUAGAAUGUUUAAAAGAACCAGGAAAAACAUCUGUAGAAUCUAAAGUACCUACCCAGAUGGAAAAAUCUACAGACACAGACGAGGACAAUGUAACCAGAACAGAAUAUAGUGACAAAACCACCCAGUUUCCAUCAGUUUAUGCUGUGCCAGGCACUGAGCAAACGGAAGCAGUUGGUGGUCUUUCUUCCAAACCAGCCACCCCUAAGACUACUACCCCACCCUCAUCACCACCUCCAACAGCUGUCUCACCAGAGUUUGCCUACGUCCCAGCUGACCCAGCUCAGCUUGCUGCUCAGAUGUUAGGUAAAGUUUCAUCUAUUCAUUCUGAUCAAUCUGAUGUGUUAAUGGUGGAUGUGGCAACCAGUAUGCCUGUUGUUAUCAAGGAGGUGCCAAGCUCAGAGGCUGCUGAAGAUGUCAUGGUGGCUGCUCCUCUUGUGUGUUCUGGAAAGGUGCUAGAAGUGCAGGUUGUGAACCAAACAUCUGUCCAUGUAGAUUUGGGUUCUCAACCUAAAGAAAAUGAGGCUGAACCAUCAACGGCUUCCUCAGUCCCCUUGCAGGAUGAACAAGAACCUCCUGCUUAUGAUCAAGCUCCUGAGGUCACUUUGCAGGCUGAUAUUGAGGUUAUGUCAACUGUUCAUAUAUCAUCUGUCUAUAACGAUGUGCCUGUGACUGAAGGAGUUGUUUAUAUCGAGCAACUGCCAGAACAAAUAGUUAUCCCUUUUACUGAUCAAGUUGCUUGUCUUAAAGAAAAUGAGCAGUCAAAAGAAAAUGAGCAGUCACCACGAGUUAGUCCCAAAUCUGUAGUAGAAAAGACCACCUCUGGCAUGUCUAAAAAAUCUGUAGAGUCUGUAAAACUUGCACAGUUGGAGGAGAAUGCAAAAUAUUCCUCAGUAUAUAUGGAGGCAGAAGCAACAGCUCUGCUCUCUGACACAUCUUUGAAAGGUCAGCCUGAGGUACCUGCACAACUCCUGGAUGCAGAAGGUGCUAUCAAAAUAGGCUCUGAAAAAUCUCUGCACCUUGAAGUGGAGAUCACUUCAAUAGUCUCUGACAAUACUGGGCAGGAGGAGUCUGGGGAAAACUCUGUACCCCAGGAGAUGGAAGGCAAACCUGUGCUCUCUGGGGAAGCUGCAGAAGCAGUGCACUCAGGUACAUCUGUAAAGUCAUCUAGUGGCCCCUUCCCUCCUGCUCCAGAAGGCCUUACUGCACCAGAAAUUGAACCAGAAGGGGAAUCAACAGCUGAAUAAGGUUUGAUGAAGCCAGCAAUGGCAACAAGUGAACGAGGACAACCACCACCAUGUUCUAACAUGUGGACCCUUUAUUGUCUAACUGAUAAGAAUCAACAAGGUCACCCAUCACCGCCACCUGCACCUGGGCCUUUUCCCCAAGCAACCCUCUAUUUACCUAAUCCUAAGGAUCCACAGUUUCAGCAGCAUCCACCAAAAGUCACUUUUCCAACUUAUGUGAUGGGCGACACCAAGAAGACCAGUGCCCCACCUUUUAUCUUAGUAGGCUCAAAUGUUCAGGAAGCACAGGGAUGGAAACCUCUUCCUGGACAUGCUGUCGUUUCACAGUCAGAUGUCUUGAGAUAUGUUGCAAUGCAAGUGCCCAUUGCUGUUCCUGCAGAUGAGAAAUACCAGAAACAUACCCUAAGUCCCCAGAAUGCUAAUCCUCCAAGUGGACAAGAUGUCCCCAGGCCAAAAAGCCCUGUUUUCCUUUCUGUUGCUUUCCCAGUAGAAGAUGUAGCUAAAAAAAGUUCAGGAUCUGGUGACAAAUGUGCUCCCUUUGGAAGUUACGGUAUUGCUGGGGAGGUAACCGUGACUACUGCUCACAAACGUCGCAAAGCAGAAACUGAAAACUGAUCCAGAAAUGACGCUGUCUGGGUCAACAUUUCAGGGAGGAGUCUGCCACCAGUGUAAUGUAUCAAUAAACUUCAUGCAAGCAUA